GCAGACAGAGUGAGCGAGUGAGCGAGUGAGUGAGCCAGCGAGCGGCAGCAGGAAUGACAGCACUGAGAGCAGAGACAGCCAGGGACGGUGAGGGCGGGCGAGUCGGGUCCCGGGGGGUGCCUGUGCUGGCCCUUUCUGCAGAGGCAGAUGAAGUGGGGGCCACUUUCAGGGCUUGCUAGGGUUUCUCUUGGAACCUGGGCUGCUCGACCCGAGUGGAGCACUGAGCAAGGGGGAGGGGGAAAGGGAGGGGGAGAGAGAGGGAGGAAGAGAGAGAGAGAGAGACUGAGAGAGACUGAGAGAAGCUCCUAGCAGGCUCUAGUCCAAGUGAGAGGCUCAGAUCUGUACAAUUCUGUGCCAGGGGCACAAGUGGGAUUUGGAAGAGCCAUGUGUGUGAGAAGCAAAGCUGAGGUGAUGUAAGCACCUGGGGAGGAGCACAGGCAGAGGAGGAGGAGGAGGAGUAGGAGGAGGAGGAGGAGAAAGAGGAGGAGGAGGAGGUGGCAGCGGCCGCCGCGGUGGCUGCCAGUCCAGAGCAGAAUGAUGGGCAACUCUCACCACAAGCAACCGAGGAGUAAAAGCCAAAGCAGGAUGCAUUCAGCAACAGCUGCAGCUAACUCGGGUCGGGAAAAUGCGACAGCGACUGCCCACUCGAGGUCGUCAUGGCGACAGCCAGUGAACGUGUUCCUCUCCUCGGGCAGGCCCCCGAGUGUAGAGGAGCUGCUUCGGGAGGCGCAGCUCAAUCUCCAGAGCCUGUUGCAAGAAGAAUAUGAGGAACAGUACUCGGAGGCCAGACUUGUGGGGCAGACCUUCCGCUCUUCUGAUGAGGCCACUAAGCCCACCCCCAACCCAAGGCCCCAGUCUGCCAGGCGUCUGGAGUUUAUAUUGAUGCCUACAAAACGGCAGCUGAGCGAGGAUGAGACUACCACCCAGGGUGUGAGGGCCCCCGAGGCCUCCCUGAGCCUGUCUACCACAGCCGACAAGCAAACUGCCUGGAAUAGCCUUUUCCCUCUGCCCAUCCUAGAGGAGAAGCGGUGGCCUCAGCUUUGCUCCACGCAGUCUGACAUUGUGCCCAUCAACAUCUCUGGGCAGCAGUUUGAUAAACAUGCAAGUUUGCGACACUCGUUGUUUAACACAGAGACAGCCGUGAACCCCAAGUCCACCCUGAGGCGGAGGCGGACCAUUAUUGGAUUCUCUAACUUUUCCCAGCGAGACCAAGGUCACAGCAACAGCCCAGCAGGCAGUGUGGCCCACUCUACCACCUCCGACAUCAGGCCCAGUCACUCAGUUCCAGAAGGGGUUCAUGGAAGAGUUGCAGUUGGUCAGGAUGCUCGGUUCCCAAGUCUCACCUCGCCAGUACUGAGAACUCCUUCCAGUGAGCCGGACGAACCUCACCAGGCACGGAGUGGCCCAAACCCUCCUGGCAUGGAGAGCAUGGGAAUGGUGUACAGUGUCCCCAGUUCUUGCAAUGGACCUACAGAAUCAACCUUCUCCACUUCCUGGAAGGGAGAUGCUUUUACCUACAUGACUCCAAGUGCCACCAGCCAGAGCAAUCAAGUCAAUGAAAAUGGGAAAAAUCCUUCCUGUGGGAAUUCUUGGGUCUCUCUAAACAAAGUCCCACCUCUGGUUCCUAAGGAGGCUGCUACCCUCCUUGUCGCUCGUGAUAACCCAGCAGGAUGCAGUGGGUCAGCUGGCUACCCUGAGCGCCUUAUUCAGCAAAGGCACAUGCCCGAAAGACCCUCCAAGAUUGGCCUUCUGACCAGUGGGACCUCGAGGCUGGAGACAGGCCCCGGUGGGGCCAGCAGAUUCCGGGAGCGGUCACUGUCUGUGCCCACAGACUCAGGCACCACAGAUGUGGACUAUGAUGAGGAGCAGAAGGCCAAUGAGGCCUGUGCCCUGCCUUUUGCCAGUACGAGCUCUGAGGGCAGUAACAGUGCUGACAACAUUGCCUCCCUUAGUGCCCAGCAAGAGGCCCAGCACAGAAGGCAGAGGUCCAAGAGUAUCUCACUUAGGAAGGCCAAAAAGAAGCCUUCCCCACCCACACGCAGUGUCUCACUGGUCAAAGAUGAGCCAGGCCUCUUGCCUGAAGGUGGGUCAGCACUACCCAAGGACCAGAGGCCCAAGAGCCUUUGCCUCUCCUUGGAACAUCAAGGACAUCACUCGUCCCACCCAGAUGCUCAGGGUCACCCAGCUAUUCCAAACCACAAAGAUCCAGAAAGUACACAAUUCUCCCACCACUGGUAUCUUACUGACUGGAAGUCUGGUGACACCUACCAAUCCCUGUCCAGCUCCAGCACUGCCACUGGCACCACAGUCAUUGAGUGCACCCAAGUUCAGGGCAGCUCAGAGUCUCUUGCCUCACCUUCCACCUCCAGAGCCACUACACCUUCCCAACUCUCCAUUGAAGUGGAGGCCAGGGAGAUAUCAUCCCCGGGAAGGCCCCCUGGACUGAUGUCACCCUCCAGUGGCUACUCCAGCCAGUCGGAAACACCAACACCCACUGUUUCCAUGUCCCUGACCCUGGGCCACUUACCCCCUCCAAGCAGCAGUGUCCGGGUACGUCCAGUGGUACCUGAGAGGAAGUCAUCACUACCCCCGACGUCACCAAUGGAGAAAUUUCCCAAGUCACGGCUAUCAUUUGACCUACCACUGACCUCUUCACCCAACCUGGAUCUGUCUGGGAUGAGUAUCUCCAUCCGAAGCAAAACUAAGGUGAGUCGGCACCACUCAGAGACAAAUUUUGGCGUCAAGCUGGCCCAGAAAACUAAUCCCAACCAGCCAAUCAUGCCUAUGGUUACUCAGUCCGACCUACGUUCUGUUCGCCUGAGGUCGGUCAGCAAGUCUGAGCCGGAAGAUGAUAUUGAGAGCCCUGAGUAUGCCGAGGAACCCAGAGCAGAAGAAGUCUUCACCUUGCCAGAGAGAAAGACAAAACCUCCCGUAGCUGAGAAGCCUCCGGUGGCCCGGAGGCCUCCAAGCUUGGUCCACAAGCCACCAUCUGUUCCUGAGGAGUAUGCACUAACUUCACCAACCUUGGCUAUGCCCCCCAGGAGCUCAAUUCAACAUGCGAGACCACUCCCUCAAGACAGCUACACGGUAGUGCGGAAACCAAAGCCCUCCAGCUUCCCAGAUGGCAGAAGCCCAGGGGAGUCAACAGCACCCUCAUCUCUUGUUUUCACGCCUUUUGCCAGUUCCUCUGAUGCUUUCUUCUCAGGAACACAGCAGCCUCCCCAGGGAAGUGUAGAGGACGAGGGCCCCAAGGUGAGGGUUCUGCCUGAAAGAAUUAGCCUCCAGAGCCAGGAAGAAGCUGAGAAAAAGAAAGGCAAGAUUCCACCUCCCGUACCAAAAAAACCCAGCGUGCUGUACCUGCCUCUCACUUCUCCCACAGCUCAAAUGGAGGCCUAUGUGGCAGAACCAAGGCUGCCUCUCAGCCCCAUCAUCACCCUGGAGGAAGACACCAAGUGUCCCGCCACCGGCGAUGACCUGCAAUCACUUGGUCAAAGGGUGACUUCAACUCCUCAGGCUGACAGUGAAAGGGAGGCAAGCCCUCUGGGGAGUUCUGUGGAACCAGGCACCGAAGAAAAAAGUUUAAUCAGUGAUAAAACAGCUGAAUGGAUUGCAGAGGAUGAUGAUGACGUGUUUGUGGCUUCACGCACAACUGAAGAUUUAUUUACUGUGAUACACAGGUCCAAAAGGAAGCUGCUCGGCUGGAAGGAACCUGGUGAGGCCUUUGUGGGUGGCAGAACGAGUUCCCACUCACCAAUAAAGAACACAGCUGAGUCUCCAAUCAGUGAGUCUACCGCCACUGCAGGGUCAGGCAGCAGUGCCAACCUAGAUGCUGGCAGAAAUGACGAUUUCAAGGCCUUGCUACAGAAGAAGGGAAGUAAGGCAACUCCAAGGUCUCGUCCCUCAGCAGCUGAACUUCUGAAGACCACUAACCCACUGGCUCGGAGAAUUAUUGCACAAUUUUCAAAAGACUAUGAAACCACCGAUAACCCCAGUACCUAAGCCCUGGGCUCAACAAGCAGGGUUUACUUACUAAACUUGAGUAGAGAAGGGGGAAGAGAAAGGGUCUUUAAACAGAACCAUGGGAACAACAGAGCCUACAUUUCUUUUAUAUUAACUCACACUCUGGACAGCAGGAGAGAGGCUACUUCAUCUAGAGCUAAAAUCAUCUGGCACUUAAUCAUCUUCAGACAUUUUUAUGUUUUCAUACUUAUAAGCUUGUCAUGACUGACUACCGAGUUUCUUCUUAUUUUCCCCCAGUGGUGUGCACUAACUAAGAAGAAAUUUUCAGAUGUCAGGGCACAUGUGCCACUUUUUCAAUUCAGUGACCCGGCUGCUCCAUCCCUGGCUCCUGUCACUGAGGAGUGCAGUGUGAGAGCAGAUUGGAGGCUGCCAAACUUGGGGGGCAUAGGGUGCCAUUGCUUAUUAUUCACUUUCCUAGGGAGGCUCUGAUGGCCCUGUGUGCAAACACAGAAAGACUCUGAUGCCUCCUCAACCACAGUUUAGCUUUCCCCUGCGCUCACAAGAGGUUUGCAGGGUGCACUUAUUUCGGCAUGAGGUUGAUUGGAUGGCUUUUGUGGUGCAAAAUAUGACUGUGACUCUGUCCUGAAACUUAAUGCCUUUUUCAGUUUGAUUGUCUACAUGGAGAUCAGGGUGAUAAGUUUCAAUAAACAUAUAGACGCCCCCCCACCCACCCCCAUUAGCUAGAAAAGACCAGGACUGGGUUGCUUUAAAUGAACCAAGCUUGACCAACAAACAAGACAGCCAUUUGUUCACUCAGAUCUAGCCGAGGUAACUCACAAGUGCACCUUGAGAUCCUCCAUGUGUCUGUCAACAGCGAUAGGCAGGAUCUGCGCCCAGCUCAUGCUGCAUUCUAAGAACUCUCAUUUCAUUUGCAUAUAAAAUUCAUUACAGGAAGUAAUUAACUGAAGGAACAGCAUCAUCAAAGGCUCAAGGAUAAUGGAAAGUAAGUGCAUCUUGCCCCCCACCAGUCAAUUCAGAUCGUGGUUUGUGGUUGGUUUGGUUUUGUUUAAAGGAAGUCCGACUCUGUUCCAAAAACCAAGAACAUAUAAACUAAAAGGAUCUAUCCAAAAUCUAAAAGGCAGUCUUGCCAGUUGCUAUGGCCCAUAAUGCACACACACACACACACACACACACACACACACACACACACAAAAGGGCUACUUUUUGCCAUUUAGGUUCUGUGUUUGACCAGCUUUCAAUUAACCUUGCUGGGGGAGAGCAUAAGAACCUGGGUAAAUGGCAUACUGAAAGAGCUUCAGAAUAAUCAUUGCGACCCCUCCCUGCCCCCACCCCCCACGAAGCUUAUAGGCACUAACUAUUCUUGUCAGCUCAAUUUUCUAAGCAGAGCAAGAGCAGUGAUUCAUUUGAUUUUUGUAUGCCUGAUUUCUGGGAGGUUGGGGAGGAAGACAAAGCACUGAGCAAAGAAAACCUGCUGACCAAUGAUGGAAAGUUAAUUGUCUACUGUCUUCAAGAGGCAAAAAGAACAGUUGAAUGAAAUUGUAGCCUGCUUCACAAAGAGAGUUCCCCAGCCCCUUCCUACUUCACCCCUCACCCAAUAGAUUCAAUGGUCAACCUCCUGGAGGAUGCAGUAAGGUUCCAGAGACAAGCAGAUCUCAACUUUGAUAGGUCGUAUUGCCCAAUGAGAAGCCACCUUUUAGCUCAACUGCCCACACUCCAGCUGGACAGAGCAGCUGAAAAACCACACUAAGUACUGAGAAAACUUGGGCCUCUCACAAGAGAAGCCCUAGGCCUAGGCCCUUUGUUGUUAUAGUUCUGAAUCUGAGACUUCUGGAAACAGGCCAGGCCCACCAACUCCCUUGCAACCAGCACUUCGACACUUAAAAUAAUAAAACAGCUAGGCUCAGUUGCUUUUGAAAGUACUAGAACUACUUGGUGUGAAGUUCUUAACCAAAUUCCAAAUUCCAGGGAUUUUGCCCAAAAUAAAAUCAAUUCAUCCCUGGCCUCAGUUUAUAUAUGAAUGCCACAUUUGUCUGCUCCAGACUUAGAAUUCCAAAAAACAGACAUUUUCCUCUGUAGUAAAUGAAGGAGCGUUUGUGCUUUUGCUUAGCAAAAAUGAAAGGACACCAGGGUCUCCUUGGGAACCAUUAUGACUGGUUGAACGUUAAAGCUGAGUAUGGGACUCACAUAGUAUAGGCCUUGUUACUUCUGUGGACUUUUCUGGAAGUUUCUUGUUUACUACUUCUAAUGGGUUUUGCCUCUCCCCUCACCUUGCUACCUCUGGAGGUUUUCCCAAAAGAUUCUGAACCUGAAUUCUCAGACACCUUGAUGUUUGUCAGUUACCUUUAGUCUUGUUUUCCUCUACAAUACUCUAUAUGCCUGGAAUUUUUAGAAUAUCUUCUACAUCAUCACUGUGGCCCACGCAGUGGUGUUCCCAUUAGCACAAGAGGAUUUGGGGCAGAAAUCAUAUGGUCAGAGAGAACAUUUAAGACCGGAAGUAUUCAUUUAAUUUUUUAAAUUAAUUUUUUGUAAAGAUGGGGGUUUUGCUAUGUUGCCCACGCUGGUCUUGAACUCCUGAGCUCAAGCGAUCCUCUCGCCUUGGCCUCCCAAAGUGCUGGGAUUAAAGGAGUAAGCCACUGCACCUGGCCUCAUUUAAUAUUUUGCAACAGGUAGACGUCCCAAAUAAACAACCAAACUGUAAAAUUUCUACUAAUCACUAAUUAACAGAACACAAAGCAUCUUCCCCACUCCUAACACUCAACCUCUCUCCUACCUUUGAUUAUCAUAACUCCACUCUCUCUCCCACCCAGGCACUUACCACAAUGUUUGCUGCCUUCUGCACCUACGCUGCUGAGACUGGAGAAGAGAGGCUGAAAGCCCCUCUCAGAAAGGCUUGCAGAGAACCCACCACUACUACAAUUACUAGUAUAAAUAAUAAUGAUAAUAAUUUUUGAAGGUGGAAUAGAGAAGAGAUUUGAGUGAAAUGAAGUUGGCCCUAGGAGCUCAGCUUCCAUUUCAAGUCGUCCCUAUCCUCUUUUUUCCUCCCCAUUCCAGUUAGUAGCAACAGAUGGCUCUGCUAGCCUGACUUUGAUCUAGUCACCAUCCCCAGGAGCGGAGGUUAAUUGUUAACCAAGGAUGCUUUGCAUUUGGUGGGUAGUCAGUACAUGUUUUUGAGGGUAGUUAUUCUUGGUACAAUAGCAAGCUUUGCUGGUGUCUCCUCUCCUUAUCCUGUACUACUUGGCCUGCCUCAGCUCCUGACUGGGCCUCCCCCACCAGCCCCAACUUAUUCCUCAGCCCCAACUUAUCCCUCAGCCCCAAAUCCCAUGAACUGCAUCCCUAGCACAACAACUCACCCAUAAAGGAAGUGAGACAACAGGAAGCAAAAUAAUUAAUGUUAGCUUAAUGACCACAAACUGACCAGUUGAUCUGGAUAAAUUACCUUGAACGUGCAAAGACAGAGGAGAUCCUACCAGGCUCUCCUAACAAGCACUGCACCUGACAUCCAGUGUAACUAUCUGGACAACACAGACCCGAUUGCAGUCUCUCUGUACCUGUCAGUCUGAGCAGAUCUGUCCACGCACCUGCCCUCUUCCUCAUCAAUGAACAAGUUGGGAAAAAGAUGAGUUCAUGCUCAGUGCUCUGUUCCUCACUCGUUCCACCUUCCAUUAUCAAGUCUGUGACACAAUGGUGAGCUUUCGCUUUAAUAUGAUUUGCUAGGGCCAGGACUAGGGUGAGGUGAGCGAGGCACCUAGGGCGUAAAAUUCAAAGAGGUGCCCGCUCUCAGGGCCAUGCAAGUGCCUUACCCUCGUCCCAGCCCUGUGAUUUGCACUCUUUAAAGUAAUAUCAGUUUAUCUUCUUCCUAUGAACAAGUAUAGUCCUUCUGAUUUGGGGUCGGGGGUUAACUCCCUAUCUCUUGUUGCACCAAAUAUUUUAUUGCUACCUAUUUUUCCAUUGCUAUAAGUCUUUGUGUGCCUAUACAUUAAAGAAUCUUUAAUAGUGUUAAUAUCGGAAAACAUAGUUGAUUUCUAAGUAAUAUGCUCCAGGUGGCAAGUUAACACCCAUUUCAGCAGGGAUGCUCCCAAGGCCAGCCCUUCAACAAAAGAGUGACUGAGUUGACGGUCUGUCACCAGGAUCCUCCCUCUCCUCUUUCUGCUCCAUUCUCCUAAACCUUGCUUCCCAGCACCAACUCUCUUCAGUGCCUCCUACUUCCUUCUCCUCCUAAGAAAAACCUGCUCUCAGGAAAGGGAUAAAUUCAUUUACUUUGAGAUUAUAAGGCUUAAUGCUACCUCUUUUGAGGGUCAGUUGCAUUUUAACAAGGGAAAAGCCUUAAGCCAAUGGAAUGAAGUUCUACUUGCAGAAUGUUAGGCAUCAACUAGUUGUAGAAGUGUAUUUUUCACCAUGGAAAGGCCAAAUUCCCUGACGCCUAACUCCAGAAUAUAGAAAAUAUCUUAAUCGCCUGGAAUCAUUUGAGUUACUAGCUGAUGGUCAAUUAAAUUGUCCUGAUAUCCAAUGCUAUUCAAUAUGGUUACUACCAAGGGACUCUCAGAAAUGGCUACUAAAAGCCACUGAGAAGGCCUAGAUCAUUCAUAUUGUACAUUGACAUUUUUACAUAAAUGGAAUUAAUACUACUUACCAUUUGAGUAAAGAACACAAGGAAUUGAAGAGUCUGUGAAAAUAUGUCCUGUUUGUGAAAGGUGAAACUGUCCAAUCCAUGUCCAAUCAAUGUCAGUCGUCCAGUAUUGGUGGUGAUUAUUAAACUUAUUGGAGGUACAACUUUACCUCCAAUAAGCUUACCUUUACAAGCUUCUGCUUUCCCUGCUUCAUCUCUGUUAUGGGCUAUCAGUCCAGCUUGGUGUGAAAAUGAGACUAUAUCUAUACCACAGCCCCCAAUCCUUUCAAAGGCUUUGCAUGUAUUUCAGCUACAAGUGACAAGGAUAUUAGGGAUUUAAAAGGAUAAGAGAGUGGGAAAGAUGUAUAAGGAAGUGCCUUUGUCAAAAGGCAGCAAAAAGUAUAAUGAUAUAAACAUAAUAUGAAAUAAGCAAAUUUUAGAAUACUUUGAAACAGAUUUAUAGAGGAAUACAUAGUAAAUAGUUAUAGACACACAUUUGGGGCAUUUUUAAUAAGGUUAGCAAGAAGAAAUUUGCAUGAGUAAUGAGCAAUGUGAAAUGGGCAUUAUACUUUUGUUCAGUAAAGCCCAAAAUCUAGGCCAAUGGUUCUCAAAGUGCAGUUCCAGGAGCAGCAACAGCAGCAUCCCUGGAGAGGGAGAAAGAGAGAGAGAGAGAGUGUAUGUGUGUGUGUGUGUGUGUGUGUGUGUGUGUGUGUGUGUAUGUGCAUUCCAGUGAUGUUACUCCUUCAAGCCCCUGAAUCACUAUAGCCACGACUCUCCAACUGAUUCCAACCUUUACCAUUAUUCUGGCUCUCAUCAUAAGGACCAGUCUCUGGCCAAGAGGUGUAUAUUGUUAUCUUGGUCAGGCAUAUGUUUGCUUGGUUUUAAGAAAUUAUCAGAUUGAGGAGUCUCAUGUUUUAUGGGACUCCGGUGCAUAUGCUCGAAAAAAAUUAAAAAGAACUUAUCAUAUUGGAUCAACAAAUUGCUCAACCUGCAAAAUCUUUGAUUAGACUUAGCCAGCCCAUCUGGCCUGCUUUGGGUUUAAAAAAAAAAAAAAGAUUUUUUUUAACUCACAAAUGGAAAAAAGGGAAAGGUGUUAAGUUUGUUUGGUAUUGCCAGCUCUUAAAUACCUGUCUUUACCGUGGUGGCUGUUCUCCAGUAAGGCUCUGGCAGAAGUAUAUUUGAUUUUAAGAUUUUUGCCUAAAUAGUAGAAUUUGAUAGCAACGAACUCCAAAACAAAAUCUGAACUGGAACAACUAGUUAACCCCUCUCAGCCUCUUUGUAAUGCCAAGCUUUAUAGACAUUUAUUCCUUAGGUGGUCUUGAGCUUUUUCUAACAUCCAAUUUUAUAAAAUGUUGUGCAUGCAAACGCAGCAUUGUGCUCAUUGUACAAGUCACCUCAAACUCAUUCCUUCCCCCAUGUGUAUCAUGGCGAAGAAAUAUCAAUAUAUGUAUGUGCUGAGGUCUUCUGAUGAAUUGUAAAUUACAAACCUUUUCAUUCAUUUUUAAAUGAGAUAUAUUUACCCUGGCUAGUGGUUAAAGUUUUAUUCUUUUUAUUAUAUUUCACUGCUACUUUUUUCUACUGACUCCAAAGCUUACUUUGGGCUAUAUUUCUUAUUUCUAGAUUGUUGUAUUUAUCUUAUUUCUAUAUUUAUCUGCAGUCUUGGAAUGUUAGAGCUGAAAGGGACCAACCUCUCUCAUUUCACACAUGAGGAAGCUGAGGCCCAGAAAGGUCAAAUAACUUAUAUACAAGGUCACACAGUGAGUCAGUGGUGGGGCCCAGCCUCAAUUCCAGGUCUCCUGCCCUUGGGCCCAAUCUGGUUUCAUUUAAAGCACUACAAUUUAUAGAAGACCCACAGCUGGCUUCUACUUUUAUGACACAUGAAUUUCCCAGGUAUUUCAAUGAACUAAUAUAUAUGCUUUAAGGGAAAAUGUUCAAGAGUUCUUUAAUUCAUUAAUCCAAAGACAAAUUGGAUUUUCAGUUUAUAAACAUUAGUUUCCCUCCAAAUUCAAUAUGUGCACCCUACUUAGUACAAUGGAUGUUUUCCCUAAAAGUUGUGUGAAAAAUGAGUUUUUUAGAUAUCAAGUAUCAUUUUUUAGAGGUAAACUUCCUAUGUAAGGGAACCUUCUGGUGACUUCUUUUUGAAAAACCGAGAUUCCUCUUGUCAUUGUCCCAUAAUGUCUCUACUUUUUUUAGUGCAAACUUUUGUAUUUGGUGUUUAUUUAAAAGUAGGGUACAACCCAACCAAUAUUAGCUUUCCCAGAGUCUACUUUAGCCUUCCCUUCUUAAUCUUUAUGAGAAAUUUUCAGACUGUUAAAUGCUCAUGAGAUAUUUAGUUGUGUUCUAGAAAUUUCACCUGGCUUGAUAUUCUGUCAAUCCCUGGGCUCAAAUUCCAGCUCCAUCUUAUCAAACAAUAACAGAAUUCCCUAAUCAGUACUAAGCUCCGCAUGCAGUCUCUUUUCCAGAACAUUCUUUGCCUAAUGUUCCUUAGUGUGGCUCUCUCUUUAGUUGGGGCCUCCUUCCUUAGUACAUGCAUACCUUACUAUUCUGUGGAAUUGCAAGCCAUGCAUCUUUUAGAGCCACACUAGUCAAAUUGAUUGGCAUUUCCAUUUAUUUUCCAUUGUUCCCUUGUUUCUCCUGGACUUCCUCUCGUUUCUCUUUUCGAGGAUGCUUAGAGGCUUCUCACCAGAGAUUGGUGAGGUUUCCCCCAUCAUCUAGAUGGGAGAUUGACAAAUUCUGUAAAGGUUAAGACAGUAACUAUUUUAGGCUUUGUGGGCUACAUGUGGUCUCUGUAGCACAUUCUUCUUUGUUGUUGCUGUUUGUUCAUUCGUUUGUUUUGCAACCUUUGGAUAAUGUAAACCACUCUCUUUUUUUUUGACAGAGUCUCUCUCUGUAGCCAGGCUGGAGGGCAAUUGUACAAUCUCGGCUCAUUACAACCUCCACCUCCCGGGUUCAGGCAAUUCUCCUGCCUCAGCUUCCCGAGUAGCUGGGACUAUAGGUGCGUGCCACCAUGCCCAGCUAAUAUUUUUUUUUUUUUUGUAUUUUUAGUAGAGGCAGAGUUUCACCAUGUUGGCCAGGAUGUUCUCGAUCUCCUGACCUUGUGAUCCGCCCACCUCGGCCUCCCAAAGUGCUGGGAUUACAGGUGUGAGCUACCGCACCCUGCCAAUAUAAACUAUUCUUAGCUCAUGGGCUAUGCAAAGCCUUAGGCUGACCCCUGAUCCAGACUGUCUUCUGAGACAAGCAUUUCUGUGAGCUGCCCCAUGUGAUAACUGAGUUGUGCAGUAGCUGAUGUGGUUUAUUGCCUUCCCAUCUACUGCAUUGUCAGACCAGACUGACUGCACAGGAGCAGGUGGAGGGGGGCUGCAUAUGCCAACCAUUACUCUUCAAUAGAGUGUCCUUCAUGAGCUCUCUCUCUCUCUCAUUACUGACUACCUCAGUGUAGAAACCCUCAUUUUUUUCCCCAGACCUAUCCUUGUUACCCAAUGUGCCUCUGCUUCCCUGGGUUUGGGAUAAACUGGAAGGAGAGAAUUUCUGAGUUCUCUUACUUAUUUUGUUCCAUAACUUCUCCCUCAUAUCUGUGGUUGGAGACUCCCACCCUUGUCCACCCUUUCCUGCCUCAUACUAGUAUCAUGAGUUUAGGGCUGUCGUUGGAAAGUCUGGCAGCCCAGGCCAUAGGAUUCCAGUUCAGCCUACGAUUUCCUAGGGAAAUCACCAGGUUCCAAAGGCUGGUUUUUAAACCUAGAAUAUCCAUGUAUCCAUUUCCUAAUGCAGUUUGGACCUGUUCUAGACAGAGCACUCAGCCUUAGCAAGAAAACCAAUGAGGUGCAGAAGAUAUUCUGUGCCCACAGUUUUUCCCUGCCUUCUGGACCCUCAGCCCCUGGGAUGGGCUCCUUGGGAUUGCCCAUGCAACAACACAGCCACAAGACAUUCAGCACACCACCUCCUCCUGUGUUUUGAAUCUCUAAAUGAAUUCUGUUCUAAAGCUUCUUCACGUCUCUCUCCAUCCUGCUCCCAUCUCCACCUCUAAUGCUUCUUGGGAGUCUGAAGCUCAGAUUCACAUUUUCACAUUUUCUCGUAUAAACGUUGUGGGAUAAGAAUGGAUGAUAUGUAUGUGUCUGUGUGAGUUUGGUUUCUCAACCUGGACUGUGAGGGCUAAUUCACAAAUCACACCAUACAUGCGUGUGUGCAUGCGCGCGCGCACACACACACACACACACACACACACACACACAGUCCAGCACCCUCAUCAGUUCUCUGGUUUAGGUCCAGAUCUGAUGGGACUGGUCAAGAAGGGGAUGGUGGGGGCUCCUGAAGCAUUUGCCCUUUCUUGCCUCUUGAGACCUUCUUUCCAUUGGCAAUUCAAAACAGGCUGACAUACAGAGGGCUAGCACUCUAAUUUGAUGUGGACUCAGCCACUCAGACCUAGGUCUCAGGCUGCAGCUUAUCCUAGCUCAGCAAAUUGCUUCUUAGAAUCUUUAGCUUGAUUUCUGUCAUUUGAGCCCAGGGAUCUACCCACUUACUGAAAUCUAAAUUUUAAAAAAUCAGUGAUGAAAGUAAUUUUCAGGAUUUCCCUAUUUAAAAGCAUCCAUGAAACAGUUCCUUUAUGCCUUCUGUUUAGGAUUUCCAGAAUUAGGAAGGGAAACCAGGCUUGUGCCUUGGAUCCAAAAGCAGCAAAAAUACUACACUUGCCAAAAGCAAACUGAGGAAUGAGCAUUGGCCAGUCCUAGUAUGCAGUCAAGAGGUGGACUUUUGUUAAGUUAGCCCUUACCAUUUAGUGCUUACUGAAUGCCAACAAUGCACUUAGAAAAAUAAGGGAGACAAGAAUUUACAGACCAUACCCUAAACUGGAAGGUACAGGAAAGACACAUCUCCUAGAGCUGGGAAUGUGUCCCUAACAUUUCAAGAAGAAGCAGAAAGUAGGAGAGAUCACGAUCUCAGUCUUUUUAGGAUUCCAACACAAAAUGGAAGGGAGCCCUCUGUGGGGUGAUAUUACAAAGGGUUUUUCUUGUCUUUCUUUAAAAAAAAAAAGGCAUUCCUUACUGGCUUGCUACCAGCAAUUGAACUGUAUUCUUUAUAUAGCUAGAGCUGUUUGUGUCUUCUUAAAAUAAACUUUUUCUGUUAAAAUCA